CUCACCUGCUCCUCUACCUGCUCCACCCUCAAUCCACCAGAACCAUGGGCUGCUGUGGCUGCUCCAGAGGCUGUGGCUCCGGCUGUGGGGGCUGUGGCUCCAGCUGUGGGGGUUGUGGCUCUGGCUGUGGGGGCUGUGGCUCCGGCCGUGGGGGCUGUGGCUCUGGCUGUGGGGGCUGCAGCUCCAGCUGUGGGGGAUGUGGCUCCAGAUGUUAUGUGCCUGUCUGCUGCUGCAAGCCCGUGUGCUCCUGGGUGCCAGCCUGUUCCUGCACCAGCUGUGGCUCCUGUGGGGGCUCCAAGGGGGGCUGUGGCUCCUGUGGGGGCUCCAAGGGGGGCUGUGGCUCCUGUGGGGGUUCCAAGGGGGGCUGUGGUUCUUGUGGCUGCUCCCAGUCCAGCUGUUGUAAGCCCUGUUGCUGCUCCUCAGGCUGUGGAUCAUCCUGCUGCCAGUCCAGCUGCUGCAAGCCCUGCUGCUGCCAGUCCAGCUGCUGUGUCCCCGUGUGCUGCCAGUCCAGCUGCUGCAAGCCCUGUUGCUGCCAGUCCAACUGUUGUGUCCCUGUGUGCUGCCAGUGUAAGAUCUGAGGCUCUGGACCCAGACCUUCAGGUUUCUCCUGUUUGGUGAAAGCAUUUCUUAUGGUUCCCUGAGUCAGUUCGUCCCACACAUCCUCCCUGAGGCACCUGCACCUGCUCUAGCUCACCAUCCAUGCACACACCUCCUUCCAUGGCUCAGCUCUCCUCUGGGCCCUGCCUUCAGCCUCCUCACUCCAGAAACGUGUGUUUCCCUGAUGCGGGAGGUGUCCUCGCCUGGACGCAGGCACCCAGCCGACUGCCACGAUGUUCCCUGCACUUGGGUGUGGACCAUCUUCUUCUUCUCCCUGGGCUGACUGAGAUGCAAGGUCUGACCCCACAAGGCCAGGCCGACGUUUCUGAGUGAUCACUAAGAACCAGCUUCUCAACCACCAUCAGGACCCUGGAUCCUCCUGGGCCGCUGCCUGUUCUCCUGUGGCCCAAGUGUGACCAGGAAGGUCUCUUUCCUUCCUGUUGUCUCCAUCUGUUUAAAAAAAAAUAACAAAAUAAUGAAUGAAUUUCCUUGCAAUAAAGCCUCUCAUGUCUGUAAAUCAA